AUUUAGAGUGAAACGCUCAUGUGCAGUGGAUGCUGUGGUGCUCCACCUCCAAUCCCUCUUCAGGUCCGGUGCCCUGUCCUCCAGAUGCUGGGCACACUGCCUGCCGAUUUUCACAGCUGCACCCCUCUCUGGGAACUGUGGACAAGUGAAGGGCCAACCCUGCUCCAGAGCUCCCUGCAGGAUCCGGAAAGCUGCCAGGUUUGGGACGCCUGGAGUGAGAGGCAGCUCCACAAGCGCAGUUGCUGUGCAAGCUGCUCUUCCACUGUGGCCACAGAAUCCAGCAGAUGUGAAGGCACUAUGCUUAUCAGUGGACUUUCCAAGUUGGAGGCCUCACUGUUGCUUCAAGUGUGGUAUGGCAGCACCCAUCUGCUGUGUCCAUCUACACUUUAUUAUAUAUCUAUGCACCUCAUCAGGGAAGCACGGGAACCCGCAGGCACUGCUAGUAGGAAGGCAAGCUGGCCUGGCCAUUCUGGAGAAGAACAUGGCAGUAUACUCAGUCACAUUCCAGUCGCACAGCCUGUGAUUUGGGUAUGCAUCAUGGAUAAAUGUUCAUUGUAGUGUUAUUUAGGAAAUCCAGGAGCUGGAGAUGGAAAGCAAUGUGCUUGAACUAGGUAGGAUGUAUACAGCUCAAAUGGGCCAACUGUUAAAUUUUCAGGAAUUUGGUGAGCUAGUUUUUAUACCCCGUUAUUAUUUAAAAUCAAAUUAUAUAAACUUACCACUAAAUAACAUAUAUUUUUAAAAGUAAUAAAUACUUAAAACACACUGCUUCCUAGUGCUUUCACUAGACUGAACCAUCAUCUUGGCUUCUGGGGUCACUGAGGCCUACUGUAUCUCCCUGGUGGACAUCCCACCUCAUGGUGUGCUGCUGCUGCCAUUCUCUGCUGGUUCUGUGUUCAGGGAUGUCCUGUUGGUAGCUUGAAAGAGGCCAUGGUGGGAAUAAUUACACUAUGGAAAUUAGCAAACCCUAUUUUGGCUAACCCUGACAGCUAAUUGUUAAACAUUUACCAGUUCACUGGAGACUAGUAUUACUCCCCUUUACAAAUGAGAAAAAUGUGGCUCAGACAGCGUAUGAAACUUGCCAAGAACCACACAACUUGUGACUGGUGCAAAUUGGAUUCAGACCCAAGCCUGUCUCAGACCUUGUACUUUACUUUGAUGAAAAUUGGAAGUGAGUUAUAACGUUUAGACUAUAAAAUUCCCAAUACUUUACCACCAACAUUGCACUUAUGUUUUUGUUUAAAAAAAAAAAAGUCUAUGGCUGCCUGCACCUGAGUACAGUGUGAAAUCAAGAAACGGCACAGUUUUUAGAAACAUCUGCUUACUGAUUGAGCUUCAUUAACUCCUCAUGUGAGAUCCCAGUCCUGAACCACAGGUGCUGUUGCUUACAGUGCGUAAGAAAAAUAAAUGAGUUCAGCUUCCAGGUUAGUGCUGUGAGGUUACAUAAACUAAUCAUUAAACAUGACAGCUAAGAUAUUUUAGCUACUGUUUAACUUUAAAAGAUUUGUUAAUAAAUAAUGCUAUUGCACA